AGUCAGAGAAAUAAUCGCAGAGCCUCAAAUAUCUCCAAAAUCUGAUACCAAUCCUUUUGAUUGUGAAUUAUAUUCUGUAGCUACCAAAGAAGGUAAGUUUUUAUUUUUUCUACUCUAUUAACUUUCCCUUGGACAACUGAAUAUUAAGAUGACUAUGUAAGGAGGUUAUCAGACCAAGGCCUCACACAUCAGGAUAAAAGCACAUGCCAUAGAAAGAACAUUUGUGUCUCAAAAGGUGAUACCAAGACAAGGCUGUGGGAUAUAUAUGGGCACAAUGGUUGAUACCUUCAAAGACUUCAUACAUGGUGUGGAGGUUUUUGGAGAUUUUAAUUUAUAAUGACAAUCUUUCCAGUUAGGAGAAUUUUUGGACUGUAAAGUUAGCCAAACAACUUUUCAAUGAUAAUAAAUGUCUAUAUCUUACACAGGGGGAAUACAGUUUUUGUUUGUUUUAGUUUUUUCUCUGUCUAUUCAUAUAGGGGCAUCAUAUGUCUUUAUCAUUAAAAACUGAUUUAGAUAGGCAGUUGUAGAGAAAUUUAAUGUGUGGGAAUUUAAAGUUUUAAAAAGAUGUAGCAAAAUAUAGAUACAUUUAAGACCCACUGCACCAAUGAAAAAGGGAAAUUAAUUAAACUAGAUAACUUUUAUGGGUACUAACCAUUAAAAUUAAAAUUUUAGUCAUUGUAAAUUACAUUACAUUAUAAUAGUUUUCAAUCUAUUGUUAAGUUAAAUAUUUUGGGUAACAAUUGUAUUUCACAGUUGUUCACACUUUGCAUAAUUUUCUAAGGAAAAUGAGUCCCUUAGGGAGAAAAUUGUUCUUAAAUUUUAUUGUUGGAUAAUGUUGCUGUACUAACAUGGUUUACUGAAGUGGAUCUACCAUGGGUGUUUAGGUUUUUGUUCUUUACAAAAUGUAUUGGGUGAAAUUUUCCAUAUCACUGGUGAACUUUUCAUGCUAAUUUUCCAGUCCCUUAGUUUAAAUAUUAUGCAUUUUUUCCUGCAAAUCUAUCUUGAAUCUGAAAAGGCCCCAGAAGGAAUUAGCGUGAGUCCAGAGUAGAUGGACUGCAAAUGUUACACAUAUUUCAAUAUGUAUCCAGCUUUCAAAAAUAGCUUAUUGAAAUCAAGGUUGAACCACAUGAAAUUUUGGGUUUUUUUGGAUGUAAAAAAUGGUUAUAUAUUGGCAUUUUCAUAUCAUCCAAUCUAAUAUCUUCCUCUAGUGAGGUUCUGGCAAAAAAAAAGUAUGAUGACCAGAGUUGUUCACUCUUUUAAGCUUUAUGUUUCAAAAUAUUUUUAAAAUUUAAAACCAUCUAAGUGCAUCCCAAAAAACAUUGGAAAAUUUUGUAGGCUAGUUUUGUUUAACGAUUUUUCUUCUAUAGAUUUAUUUUUAUGCUAUGCCUUACUCUCCAAUUAGAUUUUAGCCAUCCAAGAAAGGUACCUUGUACUUCUAAGCAAUUCUCCCAUCACCUGGACGUUAACUGCAGCCCACACUGCAGUGUCUUGACUGCAGUAGGCACUCAGUAAAUAUUUAUUGAUGGUCCUGAUUAUGGGAUGAUGAAAUAUGCUAAAGGUAACUUAAACUUUUGUCAAUAAAACCGAGUUUCAGGUUAGUUUGACCUUUUCCGUAUCUCUAAAUAUUUUCUUUCAUGUCAUUUUUGUGAAAUAGCUCACGAAAGUACUUAUUGAUUCUGAAAUCCUUUUCCCCUCUGGUAUUCCUGAGCUAUCCUCACUCACACACAGCACACCAGUGCUAUUGUUUGCUGUUUUGUUAAAAUCAUUCUCAUUAAUAUUCCUCAUUCAAUAAAAAUAGUUGAUUCCCACUUAUGCACCAAACUCUAUUCUAAAGACUGCUGUUUAUUUUAUGGAGUCAAUAUCAUCAUUUUGUUUUCCAUUCCACAUAAUAGUUGGAUGCCAAUAUGAAGUGUAUAUUUAUAAAUAAUAUGUGCUUUUAUUUAUUUGUUUAUUUUUAUUUUACUUUAAGUUCUGGGAUUAAUAUGUGCUUUUAACAUUAUUGUUUAAAAAUAACAGGAGAUAUCAUAUCUUAGCACCUUCUAUAUUCUGGGCACUGUUCUAAAUGUAUCAAAGUUAUCAUCUCAUUUAAUCCCUCCACACACCUGAGGGAAGAGAGUAUUAUUCCUUAUUUACAGAUAAGGAAGCUGAGGCUUGGAAGAUUCAUAUAUCUAAGAUCACAAAGCUAGUAAAGCAGCCAAGUUUGAGUCUAAAUCCAGGUUUUAAAUAUCAUAUUGCAUGUGGGCAUAGAUGAGCAAGAACAGGUUUUCCUGAAGAUGGCCAGUCUAAGGCUUAGAAGAAGGAAGCUCGGGGAGCCUAAACCAAGAUAUGCUAAGGCAAGUUUUUUUGCUCGUUUGUUUUUGAGAUGGAGUUUCGAUCUUGUUGCCCAGGCUGGAGUGCAGUAGUGUGAUCUCGGCUCACCGCAACCUCCGCCUCCUGGGUUCAAGUGAUUCUCCUGCCUCAGCCUCCUGAGUAGCUGGGAUUACAGUCAUGUGCCACCAUGCCCAGCUAAUUUUGUAUUUUUAGUAGAGAUGGUGUUUCACUAUGUUAGCCAGGCUGGUGUCAAACUCCUGACCUCAGGUGAUCCGCCCACCUCAGCCUCCCAGAGUGCUGGGAUUACAGGCGUGAGCCACUGUGCCCGGCCUGCUAAGGCAAGUAUUGACCAUUAGAGGAGAUGACUAGUCCCAGUGGCAGGCCUUUCCUACUGGGAGUCAGCCAAGAGCUCCCCACUCUUCUGGUUCCAUUGUUCCUCCUGCAAAGUUCCAUUCAUAAAGUGGUUUCCCAUUUGAUUGUCCAAUGAUGCAAAUCUCCAGUCCUUUUUAGCACUGAGUUUCUCAUAGCCUUUUACCAUUGAGUUUCUCAUGGCUAAUGAAUGCUAAUGAAUUGGCAUUCCGAUUUAUCUAUAGGAUUCCAUGAGUCAGCCUCAUGAAAGAAGGUUCCACUCCCUCACUGUGGGUACCGUCUGGGAAUUAGACCCUUAAUAGGAGUAAUUCAGCAGGCAAUGUCUUCUCUAAUAACACUCCAGUCUCACUGAGAGCUUCUAUUCAAAACAACAAUCUAAAGGUCUACAGUGUGACUUUCAACUAAACUGAAAAAAGAAUAGAAAAUGAAUGUAUGUGAUGUACACAUUCAUUCAAAUGUUUAUCCCUAAAAUUCAUAGCAGAUUAUGACUGAUCAUUAAAGCCAAAUUAAGGGGGCAAAAUGUAUAAAAACAAAAGGAACUCUUAGGCAUAAUAGUCUUUAAAGUAAAACAUUACUACUGACAGUUGCUUGUGUGAAAGAUAUCUUUAUUUAAUAUGGUAAAAAGAACACAGGAAUUGCUAGCACUUACCGUAUGUCCAUUUUAUGUCCACCUUAAAAUAGAUAUGUCUGUAUAGUCAUCAGAUUAGCACUUUAGAAUUCAAUAAUUUCAAAGAAAUCAGAAUGGACAUUCAUUACAUGUGCUUAUCUGGCAGGAGAAUUGAACAAAUCCUUUCUAUAGGAAAAUGUAAAAUUCCUAAUAACUCCACAGGAUUGUAAGACUUGGGCUGGUAACUUCAGUGAAUACAGCAGAGUUUGGGCGAUGGGAAAAGGUACAGUUGUGUUCCUAAACUCUUAACUUUGUGAGGCAGUGACUUUAUUUCUUCUUCAUGAUUUUGCAGUAAGUUCAGUACAGUGGUUAGUUUCAGUAUAGUUCAGUGGCUAAGCUUUUGAGAGGGACAGUUCUAUGUUCUAACUCAACUUCUGCCACUUGUUAGAAAGUGACUCUUGUCAAACUAUUGGCCCUUUCAAACCUCAGUUUCUUCAUCUGCAAAACUUUAUUCAUGGGGUUGUUGUGAGGGUUAAAUGAAAAAUAUGUAAAACUCAUCAAAAUUUUAAGCACAAAAUACCAAGUCUCAGCAGAACACAUACAGUAGGAGUCCAGCCAUUAAAAUUUGAAACAGGCAGAGGCAAAAAUAUUUUGUUUAGAAGUACUUGCAUUUUCUAGCUCUUUGGCUGAGUGGACAACAUUUUGGUGUUCUUUUUCUUAUUGUUAUUUUUUAAAGCAUACGUAUAUGUUAUGUAGACUCUUUUGUAUGUAUAUUUAACUCACAAUAAAUAUUUAUAAAUAGAAAGAAAGAUAUCACAUAUAUGUGCACAUACACUGGUAAGCCCCAAUACACUGCCUCAUUUCUAAAUGACUCUAGCAUUUGUAGGACAGUGCUUUUAAACCUUUCGCACUCACGAGAUACUCUGGGGAGCUUUAAAAUAUAUGCUGAUGCUUGGGCUCCACUUCCACAUAUUCUGAUUUAAUUGAUUAGGGGUUCGGCUCAGGCAUCAGUAUUUGUAAAUAAAAGCUUCCCAGCUGAUUCUAAUGUGAAGUUAAAAUUGACGGAUACUGAUACCGAUAAAAGAGUGAGUGCAAUAGACACAAAACAAAAUAGGAGAUGUGUCUCAACAAUGGUAAGAUUGUUUUAAAAAUUAUAGUACAAUUAAAAAAAUAAUGUAAUGCAAUUAUUUAGAAAAUUCUUACAAUUUUGUAUUUUGAAAGCACCAUGUGGAUAUCAUGGGGAAAACCAGAACUUUGUUGGAUUUCCUUAACAAAGAUUUUGCAGCUUGGUAUCAUUUCCAUUUUGUAGUAUUUUGAUAUCCAGGAGAUGAAAGUGGGAAGUGGACAAUUGCCUAUAAGGCCAUGCUUUGCACCAGGGUGUCCAGAUGAGAGGCAAGUGGAGGGUAAAGUUUAGCCUGCAUUCUGUUCCCUAAGGUACAUCUCCUGGUGAGGGGUGGCUUCUAAUCAGGGGAAGAAGUCCUAUGUCUUGUUUCCUAAUGCACGCACAGGUUCCACAAGCCCUCACUUUGUUCUCAAGAGCAUAGCAUUUAUUUUGGUGCUUAAGACUGCUGAAUGUCACAAAAUAAUUUUUCCCAGCACAAACAAAUAUUCAAAAUAGUUAUGUGCACAGCCUGUUUGAGCACCAAUAAGUUUUGGCUCUGUGGCCUGUUUGGGCACUGACAUGGUUUGGCUCUGUGUCCCUACCCAAAUCUUAUCUUGAAUUGUGAUCCCCACAUGUCCAGGGAGCGACCUGAUGGGAAGUGAUUGGAUCAUGGGUGCAGUUUCUCCCAUGCUGUUCUCAUGACAGAGAGUAAGUUCUCAGGAGAGCUGAUGGUUUAAAAGUCUUUGGCAGUUUCCCUUUCUCUCCCUCUCUCUCCUGCUGCUAUGUAAGACGUGCCUUGUUUCCCCUUUGCCUUCCGCCAUGAUUGUUUUAAGUUUCCUGAGGCCUUCCCAGCCAUGUGGAAAUAUGAGUCAAUUAAACCUCUUUUCUUUAUAAAUUACCAAGUCUCAGGCACCUAAACCAAUUAGAAGGUGUGCCAUUGGCACACAGCAGGGUCCUGGUGUCUCCCCCACCAUCCAGCCACCACUCUGCCAGGUGUGAAUGUAUUAACUAUUGCUGGAGUGAGGUGAAAGGAGGCAGUCCUGCAGAAGGGCCACUGCCACUGGGAUGGCACAGGAGGGCGCUCGAGAGACUCACCUUAGUGACUCUAUCAACUGGUGAAAAUAUUUAGAUAUUUUCACAAUCGAUAUGGCCUUGCUUGUAUAUACAGGGUGAUUAUAAACUCUCUUGCCACUUAUCACAGAAGUCGAAGUUUCAUCAUUUCUUUUCCUGUAUUUGGUUUAUGUGCAACAAUAUAGGUUUAUUUUCCAGUUCUGGAAAAUAAUCAUGGUUAAUACUGACUGAGAACUGAUCAUUUCCUUUCCUCUUUAUACCAACCAAUGGGGCAGGUACCAUUAUUAAAGGGGGAGGAAAUAGAGGUUAAAUAACAUGCCCCCAAUCAGUAGUGGGGAAAUGAAAGAAUCAGGAUUCAAAGCCAGGUUUGUCUGGGUCUUGGGACCAGCUCAGCGUCUGUGCUGUACUGCCCGGGACUCCUGCUGCCAAUUCUUUCUACCUCAUUAUCCCUCAACCCUGCACCAGCAAAUCCACAGGGCGUGAGAUGAAGAGAAGAGAGGACCACAGGCGAGAAAGUGGCAGCAGCAAGAGAAGAUGUACCAUGAGGAAGUUCUGGGAGGUUCUGCCCGUCUUUCUGAGAACAGGGGAGAGACAGAGCUGAGUUACAACUGCACUGCUUCUUAGCUUCUUAGUUUCUCUUCAGAAUUAGUGGCAAAGAAGAGUUUUCGAAGUCUUUAGCAUGUAUUAAACGAAGAAUUUUGUUUAUAAGAAAAAAUUGUGGAUCGUUCCCAUGUUUGUCUGGAAAACUCUUGUUAAACUUUUGUGCAGCUAGUAAAUUAAGUCACUGUUUAUUCUGUGUAGUGGAAAGCAUGCUUAAACUCUAACUCAGGAGACCUGAUUCCAGGAAUAGUUAAGCCUGAGUUCAUUAUAAACCACUUAAGUUAUCUGUGUCAUUAUUCUAGUCUGUUAAAUGGAGGGCUUGAGCUGGUUUCUUGUAAGGUGGGAUUUGGCUAAGUGCUCUUGGAUACAGUUGCUCACCUCUUUGAGCCUCAGCUUUCUUUUUGGUGAUUAUUUAAUCGCAUGUGAUAACAAAUACAGGGUGUUUUGUGUAAUGCCUGGAAUGGCACUGAGAUUGUCUCCACUACAGUAAGGAGGUGGUUUAGAAAUUAGCUAAUUUAUUAAUUAAUGGCCUAUAGAGCUUCAUGUAGGUUGGUACUUCAAAGUCCCAUUCAUAUGGAUCAUGUUCAUAUUUAUAUAUUCAUCACUUUUAUUUCAAAAUCUCUUUUUCUGCUGAGAUCAACUGAGAUUUCUAGAAAGCAGUCCUAUUGUCAGCACUUUGCCCAGUACAUUUAGUAAGAACUUGACUAGCAUUGACUCAAACAGUUCUCUUAGAAGGGCUGGCACCUUUUGUUUCAAUUUUUUUAAACAUUAACUGCCCAUAAUAAUUGAAGCAUGAAUGCACUUUCUUUGGAUUAUGAAACAAAUCAAUCACAGACAUGGGAAUUAGGUGUGUUCUCUUGCUUUGUUCAAUAUCAUGCAUUUUUUUUGUCUGAGCUUUCACUGUGUCCCCAGAACUGUGCUUGGUGCUAACAGUGGCCCCACAGAGUACGGCUUUAUAUUCAAGGAGAUGACAAUCUUGUUGGAGGAAAAACCUUAUACAUAGAACAAUUAAGGAACAAUGCAAGGGAAACACACAUUGCAAGUUUUGAUUGUACCUAUUUUAUGGCUAUGGUAUAAAACAAAGCACCUGUUGUUCCUGAGAGUGAAGGGAUAAGACAAUAACUACAAAAAGGUGAAAUGAGUUAAUUCAAAAGGGAACAUUGAGCAUGUCAUUUUCCUAUUGAAGUGCUAUUAUUUGGUAUCGGCUUCCUUUGGUGGUGUUGGUUUUUGAUUCCCUCUGCCCCGGACUCUGUUGUUUAAAGAUGUUCUUUCUAUGAGGGAUCUUGGAUGCAUUUUAGCAGUGUUUCCACUGCCCUUUGUUUUAUAUUCUUUGAUGCCAUCCCAGGUACAUCACAUUCUUGCUAGAUGAGUAAAGGUAAGCAUACUUAGAAGUCAAAAAGAAAAGGCUGAAGUGGUGACUUAGACUUGAGAAAUUAUAGAUUCCAUGGAGAAAACUGUGUUUAAAUCACAGGACAGGCUGAAAACUCACAUUACCACCUGAUGGAAGUGAACUCUACUUUUAUAGGUUACUAGGAGAAGGUCAGCCUUCUGUAAAAGCAGAUAAACAAGGAUACCAUUACCAGAGUUUCAAGUAAUUUAAAUUAAGAACUGAACAUUGAUACUGAUAUGAUUUCUAGUUUAUUAUCUGUGACAGAACCCAGUAGCUUAUUGAAAAACUAUCAUGGAAGAAAUAACUAAGAAAUAACCAUUUAAAAUAUAUCAGGAUAUAAUGAGGAUGAAGCUUUAGAUAACACAAAAAGGCAAUUUCUCUUUAGGCUGAAAAAUACCAGACACAGAUAUAUCGACAGAGUGACCUGCCAGAAUCCCUACUUUCCAGCCCAUCUGAUAAAGGUCAACGAUUGAACACCCAAACACGUUGAUACACACAGCACCUGCCUGAUGAAAACCGUUAACAGUGUUUUUCUCAGCCCAGAGUGCACUGUUUUCUUAAAGUUUUGAAAACAGUAAUCUAAAUUUCCCUAUUCCAUGAGUAAAGUUCUACUUUUUUCUUUUUCACACUAAACAGCAUUCGAUGUUUUAGCUGAAAGUCAAUUAAGAAAAAUGUAUUGUGUCUGUGUUUUUCUUGCUUUCUUUUAAGCACCUCUAAAAGAACUUGUUCUUCUUCCUGAAUUGAGAACGAGGUAGGAAUGAAAGACUGAAACGGUAACUCUCAUCAUAAUUUUAUUAUUAUGACAAGUUGGGUUUAUGAAGUAUUUUUCCAAUUACUGCCUCCAAUUGUUAAAUAGGUAGAUAACAUGCCAGCUUUAACUGCCAAAAACUUGUAGUCCUUAAAAUAUUUUUUGUAGUAUUACUAUUAGUAUCAUGAACAGAAAUAGCAGUGAUAAAAAUCAAAUCAAGUUUUGUGAACACCAAAAUUCCAUUUGCCUGUGUGUGGAGGGUGGUUUAGGAUUGGUAGAAUUAAUAUUCUUUGCAAACGGCUGCACCUAGCAUGGUCGCCUUGAAGCCCUGGGAGUUCUCUAAUUUUCCUGGCUCGAGAGACUUCCAUUAAACAAGAAAAUGAGGUGGGAAAGGUCAGAGGAUUCACAGGGUAACAGGAACUGGACCUGAACCUGAGCUUCAUGCAGUCCGCAGAUUUUUUAAGUGGUUUGUUUUUUAGAAGUGUUUGUCACGACCUCUAAAUCAUUGUUAAUUUCAUCGUUAAACUGGCCUCAGAGAGAUUUUGUUUUAAAGAGACAAUGCAGUUAGAGGAUCGUGAUCUCUGAACUCAGAAGCCCAGAACUCCAAAGCUGGAAGCCACCAGAUCCUAGCAAGUGAAGCUCUGUCAAUCUGGAGCCGCAGAUUUUGACCACGUGUGCACAGCCUCCCAUCUGGGCAAGCCCUUUUCUCUCCACCACUCCACUCCACAGCUUCUGUUUCUUUUCUUUUCUUUUUUUUUCGCUGAAUUCAUCAUCCCUCCCUUUCCCAUGCCGAGACUUAAAAGGUUUCAAAUACUUCAAAAAUCAAUGAUUUCUAAAUCACCUCAGAUGACUUACAUACAAUGUUUUAUUACAUUUUCCCAGAGCAGAAUGGCAUAUUAAGAAAUGGUUUUAUUUUCAACUAUAUUUUCUCUUAGGAAUAUAGAGACAUUAUCUCAAAUUAUUACCUCGAAGAGACAGAGACAAGAAUUUUGCACCAUUCUAGUUCUCAAAUCAUUUUAGGUAUUUUAUUUCAUUUUGCCUAAAUCUCUUAGACGGUUAUUUCCUCGUAUCACUUAAAAAUUACAUUUUACUUGGGCAGGGCCUAAAGAAUUACAUUGAAAAACUAAGAAAUUAUUGGGAAAAAAUUCCAUUAGCACAACUAUCAUGAUCAGAAGAAAUUGGCUAAUUUCAGUGUCUUUUCUUUGGGCUCUUCAUAGAAAAUUGUUGAAAUGUGUCUUUCAUAAGUAACUGGCAUUCUGAAAUUGAUUUAAAGCUGUAGAGGGGAAGAAAAGCUACAUUGGAAAAAUUAAAUCUUAGGUUUGGAGAUAUUUUAAAAAACUCAACAAGUUCCAUGCCCAGAGGAGUGCAGACACUGACCCUCUUUUUCAGCUAUUAGAGGUGAGGAAAAAAAGUUGUGUGGUUGGUGUGGAGAGAGAGAGACACACGCACUUCCUUUAGCCAUCAUCCUACUAACACCUUCACAGUACAUUUUCUUGCUAAUAAUCCCAACCAUUUCUACAGGGAAAAGUGCAUGUUCCUGUUCUCUGGUAGAAGGGCCACCCAAGGAAUUCAGGUUCCUGGAAGAAGAAAACUAGGAAGGAGUAAGCACAAAGAUCUCUUCACAUUCUCCGGGACUGCGGUACCAAAUAUCAGCACAGCACUUCUUGAAAAAGGAUGUAGAUUUUAAUCUGAACUUUGAACCAUCACUGAGGUGGCCCGCCGGUUUCUGAGCCUUCUGCCCUGCGGGGACACGGUCUGCACCCUGCCCGCGGCCACGGACCAUGACCAUGACCCUCCACACCAAAGCAUCUGGGAUGGCCCUACUGCAUCAGAUCCAAGGGAACGAGCUGGAGCCCCUGAACCGUCCGCAGCUCAAGAUCCCCCUGGAGCGGCCCCUGGGCGAGGUGUACCUGGACAGCAGCAAGCCCGCCGUGUACAACUACCCCGAGGGCGCCGCCUACGAGUUCAACGCCGCGGCCGCCGCCAACGCGCAGGUCUACGGUCAGACCGGCCUCCCCUACGGCCCCGGGUCUGAGGCUGCGGCGUUCGGCUCCAACGGCCUGGGGGGUUUCCCCCCACUCAACAGCGUGUCUCCGAGCCCGCUGAUGCUACUGCACCCGCCGCCGCAGCUGUCGCCUUUCCUGCAGCCCCACGGCCAGCAGGUGCCCUACUACCUGGAGAACGAGCCCAGCGGCUACACGGUGCGCGAGGCCGGCCCGCCGGCAUUCUACAGGCCAAAUUCAGAUAAUCGACGCCAGGGUGGCAGAGAAAGAUUGGCCAGUACCAAUGACAAGGGAAGUAUGGCUAUGGAAUCUGCCAAGGAGACUCGCUACUGUGCAGUGUGCAAUGACUAUGCUUCAGGCUACCAUUAUGGAGUCUGGUCCUGUGAGGGCUGCAAGGCCUUCUUCAAGAGAAGUAUUCAAGGACAUAACGACUAUAUGUGUCCAGCCACCAACCAGUGCACCAUUGAUAAAAACAGGAGGAAGAGCUGCCAGGCCUGCCGGCUCCGUAAAUGCUACGAAGUGGGAAUGAUGAAAGGUGGGAUACGAAAAGACCGAAGAGGAGGGAGAAUGUUGAAACACAAGCGCCAGAGAGAUGAUGGGGAGGGCAGGGGUGAAGUGGGGUCUGCUGGAGACAUGAGAGCUGCCAACCUUUGGCCAAGCCCGCUCAUGAUCAAACGCUCUAAGAAGAACAGCCUGGCCUUGUCCCUGACGGCCGACCAGAUGGUCAGUGCCUUGUUGGAUGCUGAGCCCCCGAUACUCUAUUCCGAGUAUGAUCCUACCAGACCCUUCAGUGAAGCUUCGAUGAUGGGCUUACUGACCAACCUGGCAGACAGGGAGCUGGUUCACAUGAUCAACUGGGCGAAGAGGGUGCCAGGCUUUGUGGAUUUGACCCUCCAUGAUCAGGUCCACCUUCUAGAAUGUGCCUGGCUAGAGAUCCUGAUGAUUGGUCUCGUCUGGCGCUCCAUGGAGCACCCAGGGAAGCUACUGUUUGCUCCUAACUUGCUCUUGGACAGGAACCAGGGAAAAUGUGUAGAGGGCAUGGUGGAGAUCUUCGACAUGCUGCUGGCUACAUCAUCUCGGUUCCGCAUGAUGAAUCUGCAGGGAGAGGAGUUUGUGUGCCUCAAAUCUAUUAUUUUGCUUAAUUCUGGAGUGUACACAUUUCUGUCCAGCACCCUGAAGUCUCUGGAAGAGAAGGACCAUAUCCACCGAGUCCUGGACAAGAUCACAGACACUUUGAUCCACCUGAUGGCCAAGGCAGGCCUGACCCUGCAGCAGCAGCACCAGCGGCUGGCCCAGCUCCUCCUCAUCCUCUCCCACAUCAGGCACAUGAGUAACAAAGGCAUGGAGCAUCUGUACAGCAUGAAGUGCAAGAACGUGGUGCCCCUCUAUGACCUGCUGCUGGAGAUGCUGGACGCCCACCGCCUACAUGCGCCCACUAGCCGUGGAGGGGCAUCCGUGGAGGAGACGGACCAAAGCCACUUGGCCACUGCGGGCUCUACUUCAUCGCAUUCCUUGCAAAAGUAUUACAUCACGGGGGAGGCAGAGGGUUUCCCUGCCACGGUCUGAGAGCUCCCUGGCUCCCACACGGUUCAGAUAAUCCCUGCUGCAUUUUACCCUCAUCAUGCACCACUUUAGCCAAAUUCUGUCUCCUGCAUACACUCCGGCAUGCAUCCAACACCAAUGGCUUUCUAGAUGAGUGGCCAUUCAUUUGCUUGCUCAGUUCUUAGUGGCACAUCUUCUGUCUUCUGUUGGGAACAGCCAAAGGGAUUCCAAGGCUAAAUCUUUGUAACAGCUCUCUUUCCCCCUUGCUAUGUUACUAAGCGUGAGGAUUCCCGUAGCUCUUCACAGCUGAACUCAGUCUAUGGGUUGGGGCUCAGAUAACUCUGUGCAUUUAAGCUACUUGUAGAGACCCAGGCCUGGAGAGUAGACAUUUUGCCUCUGAUAAGCACUUUUUAAAUGGCUCUAAGAAUAAGCCACAGCAAAGAAUUUAAAGUGGCUCCUUUAAUUGGUGACUUGGAGAAAGCUAGGUCAAGGGUUUAUUAUAGCACCCUCUUGUAUUCCUAUGGCAAUGCAUCCUUUUAUGAAAGUGGUACACCUUAAAGCUUUUAUAUGACUGUAGCAGAGUAUCUGGUGAUUGUCAAUUCAUUCCCCCUAUAGGAAUACAAGGGGCACACAGGGAAGGCAGAUCCCCUAGUUGGCAAGACUAUUUUAACUUGAUACACUGCAGAUUCAGAUGUGCUGAAAGCUCUGCCUCUGGCUUUCCGGUCAUGGGUUCCAGUUAAUUCAUGCCUCCCAUGGACCUAUGGAGAGCAGCAAGUUGAUCUUAGUUAAGUCUCCCUAUAUGAGGGAUAAGUUCCUGAUUUUUGUUUUUAUUUUUGUGUUACAAAAGAAAGCCCUCCCUCCCUGAACUUGCAGUAAGGUCAGCUUCAGGACCUGUUCCAGUGGGCACUGUACUUGGAUCUUCCCGGCGUGUGUGUGCCUUACACAGGGGUGAACUGUUCACUGUGGUGAUGCAUGAUGAGGGUAAAUGGUAGUUGAAAGGAGCAGGGGCCCUGGUGUUGCAUUUAGCCCUGGGGCAUGGAGCUGAACAGUACUUGUGCAGGAUUGUUGUGGCUACUAGAGAACAAGAGGGAAAGUAGGGCAGAAACUGGAUACAGUUCUGAGGCACAGCCAGACUUGCUCAGGGUGGCCCUGCCACAGGCUGCAGCUACCUAGGAACAUUCCUUGCAGACCCCGCAUUGCCCUUUGGGGGUGCCCUGGGAUCCCUGGGGUAGUCCAGCUCUUCUUCAUUUCCCAGCGUGGCCCUGGUUGGAAGAAGCAGCUGUCACAGCUGCUGUAGACAGCUGUGUUCCUACAAUUGGCCCAGCACCCUGGGGCACGGGAGAAGGGUGGGGACCGUUGCUGUCACUACUCAGGCUGACUGGGGCCUGGUCAGAUUACGUAUGCCCUUGGUGGUUUAGAGAUAAUCCAAAAUCAGGGUUUGGUUUGGGGAAGAAAAUCCUCCCCCUUCCUCCCCCGCCCCGUUCCCUACCGCCUCCACUCCUGCCAGCUCAUUUCCUUCAAUUUCCUUUGACCUAUAGGCUAAAAAAGAAAGGCUCAUUCCAGCCACAGGGCAGCCUUCCCUGGGCCUUUGCUUCUCUAGCACAAUUAUGGGUUACUUCCUUUUUCUUAACAAAAAAGAAUGUUUGAUUUCCUCUGGGUGACCUUAUUGUCUGUAAUUGAAACCCUAUUGAGAGGUGAUGUCUGUGUUAGCCAAUGACCCAGGUGAGCUGCUCGGGCUUCUCUUGGUAUGUCUUGUUUGGAAAAGUGGAUUUCAUUCAUUUCUGAUUGUCCAGUUAAGUGAUCACCAAAGGACUGAGAAUCUGGGAGGGCAAAAAAAAAAAAAAAGUUUUUAUGUGCACUUAAAUUUGGGGACAAUUUUAUGUAUCUGUGUUAAGGAUAUGUUUAAGAACAUAAUUCUUUUGUUGCUGUUUGUUUAAGAAGCACCUUAGUUUGUUUAAGAAGCACCUUAUAUAGUAUAAUAUAUAUUUUUUUGAAAUUACAUUGCUUGUUUAUCAGACAAUUGAAUGUAGUAAUUCUGUUCUGGAUUUAAUUUGACUGGGUUAACAUGCAAAAACCAAGGAAAAAUAUUUAGUUUUUUUUUUUUUUUUUGUAUACUUUUCAAGCUACCUUGUCAUGUAUACAGUCAUUUAUGCCUAAAGCCUGGUGAUUAUUCAUUUAAAUGAAGAUCACAUUUCAUAUCAACUUUUGUAUCCACAGUAGACAAAAUAGCACUAAUCCAGAUGCCUAUUGUUGGAUACUGAAUGACAGACAAUCUUAUGUAGCAAAGAUUAUGCCUGAAAAGGAAAAUUAUUCAGGGCAGCUAAUUUUGCUUUUACCAAAAUAUCAGUAGUAAUAUUUUUGGACAGUAGCUAAUGGGUCAGUGGGUUCUUUUUAAUGUUUAUACUUAGAUUUUCUUUUAAAAAAAUUAAAAUAAAACAAAAAAAAAUUUCUAGGACUAGACGAUGUAAUACCAGCUAAAGCCAAACAAUUAUACAGUGGAAGGUUUUACAUUAUUCAUCCAAUGUGUUUCUAUUCAUGUUAAGAUACUACUACAUUUGAAGUGGGCAGAGAACAUCAGAUGAUUGAAAUGUUCGCCCAGGGGUCUCCAGCAACUUUGGAAAUCUCUUUGUAUUUUUACUUGAAGUGCCACUAAUGGACAGCAGAUAUUUUCUGGCUGAUGUUGGUAUUGGGUGUAGGAACAUGAUUUAAAAAAAAACUCUUGCCUCUGCUUUCCCCCACUCUGAGGCAAGUUAAAAUGUAAAAGAUGUGAUUUAUCUGGGGGGCUCAGGUAUGGUGGGGAAGUGGAUUCAGGAAUCUGGGGAAUGGCAAAUAUAUUAAGAAGAGUAUUGAAAGUAUUUGGAGGAAAAUGGUUAAUUCUGGGUGUGCACCAGGGUUCAGUAGAGUCCACUUCUGCCCUGGAGACCACAAAUCAACUAGCUCCAUUUACAGCCAUUUCUAAAAUGGCAGCUUCAGUUCUAGAGAAGAAAGAACAACAUCAGCAGUAAAGUCCAUGGAAUAGCUAGUGGUCUGUGUUUCUUUUCGCCAUUGCCUAGCUUGCCGUAAUGAUUCUAUAAUGCCAUCAUGCAGCAAUUAUGAGAGGCUAGGUCAUCCAAAGAGAAGACCCUAUCAAUGUAGGUUGCAAAAUCUAACCCCUAAGGAAGUGCAGUCUUUGAUUUGAUUUCCCUAGUAACCUUGCAGAUAUGUUUAACCAAGCCAUAGCCCAUGCCUUUUGAGGGCUGAACAAAUAAGGGACUUACUGAUAAUUUACUUUUGAUCACAUUAAGGUGUUCUCACCUUGAAAUCUUAUACACUGAAAUGGCCAUUGAUUUAGGCCACUGGCUUAGAGUACUCCUUCCCCUGCAUGACACUGAUUACAAAUACUUUCCUAUUCAUACUUUCCAAUUAUGAGAUGGACUGUGGGUACUGGGAGUGAUCACUAACACCAUAGUAAUGUCUAAUAUUCACAGGCAGAUCUGCUUGGGGAAGCUAGUUAUGUGAAAGGCAAAUAGAGUCAUACAGUAGCUCAAAAGGCAACCAUAAUUCUCUUUGGUGCAGGUCUUGGGAGCGUGAUCUAGAUUACACUGCACCAUUCCCAAGUUAAUCCCCUGAAAACUUACUCUCAACUGGAGCAAAUGAACUUUGGUCCCAAAUAUCCAUCUUUUCAGUAGCGUUAAUUAUGCUCUGUUUCCAACUGCAUUUCCUUUCCAAUUGAAUUAAAGUGUGGCCUCGUUUUUAGUCAUUUAAAAUUGUUUUCUAAGUAAUUGCUGCCUCUAUUAUGGCACUUCAAUUUUGCACUGUCUUUUGAGAUUCAAGAAAAAUUUCUAUUCUUUUUUUUGCAUCCAAUUGUGCCUGAACUUUUAAAAUAUGUAAAUGCUGCCAUGUUCCAAACCCAUCGUCAGUGUGUGUGUUUAGAGCUGUGCACCCUAGAAACAACAUAUUGUCCCAUGAGCAGGUGCCUGAGACACAGACCCCUUUGCAUUCACAGAGAGGUCAUUGGUUAUAGAGACUUGAAUUAAUAAGUGACAUUAUGCCAGUUUCUGUUCUCUCACAGGUGAUAAACAAUGCUUUUUGUGCACUACAUACUCUUCAGUGUAGAGCUCUUGUUUUAUGGGAAAAGGCUCAAAUGCCAAAUUGUGUUUGAUGGAUUAAUAUGCCCUUUUGCCGAUGCAUACUAUUACUGAUGUGACUCGGUUUUGUCGCAGCUUUGCUUUGUUUAAUGAAACACACUUGUAAACCUCUUUUGCACUUUGAAAAAGAAUCCAGCGGGAUGCUCGAGCACCUGUAAACAAUUUUCUCAACCUAUUUGAUGUUCAAAUAAAGAAUUAAACUAAA